AGUCCUGCCCCUCACUUCCUCUGAGUCUGUUUCUCAGGCUCCUCGGGCCCUCAGUGCCCUGAGUUUCGGUCACUUGGCUUACCAGGCCUCUCCUCCUGCCCCCUGGACUCUGAGGUUGGCCUCUCCCGCUUGCAUCUUGGUCUUGCCUUCGUUACUCUGCUUUUCUAGCCCAUCAUCCUGGCUAAUCUCCAGCCCUGGGUAAGUUUAUGGUGCUGGGCUGGGCUUUUGGAUAAAAGGACCAGCCAUUCCCAUCCUCUAUGAGACACUUAAGGUGUCAGCAUUGUCUGGGCCCUGCAGGGUGACAGUUCAGGCCCCUCUUGGCCGCCGCCUCUCCACCCCAUUUCCAUUUUGCGGUCUCCAUAGGCCCUCCCAGCGCCGCAGCCCCGCUCCUCCUCUCUGCUGAGACACUCAGCACUCGUCUUCCUGAGUGAACUGCUUUCACUUCUCUUCAUGCCCGGGUUUCCCCUUUCUUCCUCCAGGGAGGAAGGAUCAUUCCGCUUUGUCGACCAUCCCCCCACUCCACCCACGCUUUCUCCUAUCGAUAAAAUUCACACUUGAUUCAGAUUUCCUCAGCUUUUCCUUAAUGUCCUUUCUCUGUCCCAGGAUCCCACCCAGGAUCACACAGGACAUGAGUGGGCACAUCUCGUCAGCCCCUCUUGGCUGUGGUGCUUUCUCAGGCGUUCCUUGUUUGGAUGACUGGCACUUGGGAGCAGUGCUGUGGGUCAGGGAUUUUUUUGUAGGAUGCUCUUCUCUUGGGACUUGUUUGAUAUUUUCCUUAUGACUAGACUUGGGUGAUGCAGUUAGAGGGCCUGUCUCGCCACAGCCUGUCAAGGCUGUGUUCUGUCCACAGGACUCAUUGCUAUGGAUGUGGCCUUGAACACCUGGCUGACUGAGGUGGUGUUUGCCAAGUUUCUCCUCAGUAAAGUUAUUUUCCUCCUUUCCGUACUCCACUCGUUAGAAACUGUCCCUGUGAACGGCCAUACUUGAGGGGUGGGGAGCAGCGUCCUCCCUGCUGGAGGAGGAGGAGCCACAGGCAUUCCUCGGACUCGUGGCGCUGGGUAUUUGUCUAUUUUCUGUUUAUUCAGCCACUGCUUUAUAUCAGUCUGGACUCGUGCAUGUUUACUUGAUGCUUCGGGUUAUAAAGCAAUACUAUUUUAUUUUCCUGGAAAAAGCUUUGGCCAUUGGGAGCUCUUUUACUUGGUUCCUAUAUCCCUUUCAUGAGCCCACCUGUCCCCAUGAUUGUGUGUGUGUAUUGUGAACACUUCAUUAUUCUCUGGCAAUACAAGAUGCUCCAAGCUCAUCUUGUAUAUAUAUUUAUUUUUUUUGCCUCAGUCCUGGUUCCUUUUAUUUAUUAGAGAAUGGUAUUAAAAACCAAGAUCUGUGGUGGCUCACACCUAUAAUCCCAGCACUUUGGCCGACAUGGGAAGAUCGCUUGAGUCCAGGAAUUCAAGAGCAGCCUGGGCAACUAGCAAGAUCCCAUCUUGAAUAUUAAACAACAACAACAAACCAAGAUCUGGGAAUUAGGUGUGCUGGUGGCUGUUGGUGUGUUGCUUCUAGGCCGUCUCAGCUGACAGAGCAAAUCCGAUCACAUAGGACAGUAUGCACCUUAAGAUCCUGAAGAAACGGCACAAAAUGUUCAAGUGAUGUUUAGAAAUAACUUGUGAGGGUGCGUCAGGGAAAUCAUGCAGCCAUCAGGACACAGGCUCCGGGACGUCGAGCAUCAUCCUCUCCUGGCUGAAAAUGACAACUAUGACUCUUCAUCGUCCUCCUCCUCCGAGGCUGACGUGGCUGACCGGGUCUGGUUCAUCCGUGACGGCUGCGGCAUGAUCUGUGCUGUCAUGACGUGGCUUCUGGUCGCCUAUGCAGACUUCGUGGUGACUUUCGUCAUGCUGCUGCCUUCCAAAGACUUCUGGUACUCUGUGGUCAACGGGGUCAUCUUUAACUGCUUGGCCGUGCUUGCCCUGUCAUCCCACCUGAGAACCAUGCUCACCGACCCUGAAAAAUCCAGUGACUGCCGACCAUCUGCCUGCACAGUGAAAACUGGGCUGGACCCAACCCUUGUGGGCAUUUGUGGUGAGGGAACCGAGUCUGUGCAAAGCCUCCUGCUUGGGGCAGUACCCAAAGGAAACGCUACGAAAGAAUACAUGGAGAGCUUGCAGCUGAAGCCCGGGGAAGUCAUCUACAAGUGCCCCAAGUGCUGCUGUAUUAAACCCGAGCGCGCCCACCACUGCAGUAUUUGCAAAAGAUGUAUUCGGAAAAUGGAUCAUCACUGCCCGUGGGUGAACAAUUGUGUAGGAGAAAAGAAUCAAAGAUUUUUUGUGCUCUUCACUAUGUAUAUAGCUCUGUCUUCAGUCCAUGCUCUGAUCCUUUGUGGAUUUCAGUUCAUCUCCUGUGUCCGAGGGCAGUGGACUGAAUGCAGUGAUUUUUCACCUCCGAUAACUGUAAUCCUGUUGAUCUUCCUGUGCCUUGAGGGUCUUCUGUUUUUCACUUUCACUGCAGUUAUGUUUGGCACCCAAAUCCACUCCAUAUGCAACGACGAGACGGAGAUCGAGCGAUUGAAAAGUGAGAAGCCCACAUGGGAGCGGAGGCUGCGAUGGGAAGGGAUGAAGUCCGUCUUUGGGGGGCCCCCCUCACUCCUCUGGAUGAAUCCCUUUGUGGGCUUCCGAUUUAGGCGACUGCCCACGAGACCCAGAAAAGGUGGCCCGGAGUUCUCAGUGUGAGGCGUGGCUCAUCAGACUGAAACUUGCUCACAGACUUCCAGUUAUUUAUUUGGGGUCUGAAGGAUAUCAACAGCUCAUCUGUGACCAACAGGGCAACUGGAACCUACACAAACCAAUUGCUUGCAGCAAGCAGAGUUUUAUAUAUUUAUAGUCACAGAUGGCAGAGGAAGAGGCUCUCAGUCCCCACCUGUACAACAACGGAAAGGUGUGUGGCCACACGAAGAAGCCAAACGCCGUGGCCUCCUGCAGAGCUGGGGCUUCUGUGGAGAAUACUUCGGGUUAUUACAUGGGUUAUUCAAAUCCUGGGUCCUGAGCUGCUGUUUCCAAUCAUGAAGAAAAACAGUGAAUCCAGUGAACAGGGAUUCUCCAAGCAGUCAUUUCAGGGGGCUCCUGCUGACCCCGCCACUCAGCAGUGCACUCCCCGGAUCACAGCAGGGCGUUUACAUAGAAAGACGUUUUGGUCUCGAUUAGCUCCGAUGCUUUGCACUGAAGUUGCAAAAGAUCUGUGCACUGAACAGUGAAGGUGGCUUCCGGCACACUCCCCGCUGCCCCGGAAGAGACAUCCUUUGACCCUCUCAGCAAGUCUGUGUGUGUGCGUGUCUGUGCGUGUGCGCGCGUGUGUGCAUGUGUGUCAAAAUUGCCAGUGUUGUUUAGGCAAUGUAACAUUUACCGGCUGUGUACAGCAAACAAGCUAUUUUUUAGAAACCGACGUUUCAGGGAAGAGGGGAGAGAGCCGCGGGGUCCUGCCCGUGGUUACUAUGAAUGUAUUGCUGUUGGAGGACAUCUCGAUCCAAAGAACAGCCGUUCCUGUGCGGCCCUUCGUUGCCCUCCUGCUUUCAUUUUUUAAAGAAAUCUUGAGUGCUUGAGGGCCUUGGAACUGAUUUUUUUUUUUUGUUCCAGCCAAAUUAGCAGUGUAUAAAUGGCACCUAGGUAAGAGCAGAGCUGCGGCUCGGUGACUUGAUACUUGGGGCAGCCCGAUGCUGUGUGUGGGGCAGGGGAGGCAUCCUUACUGGAGAGGCAGGGCCCAGCCAUUGGGCACCUCUGGGAAGGGGAGGGGACCAUGAGGCAGCCAGCCCCUGGCAGGGGCGACUGUGCCACCGCAGGCAGCGCUCCAGUCGGGAAUGGCCAGGAUGGCGCCCUCUUGUUGGAGUUUUUGGUUAGCUUUUACGUUUUCUUCUCCACCCACGGCACAGGUGAUAAAAUAGGAUCCUUGGUGCGGAGCUUAAAAUUAUGCCAGAAAGCCAACAGCUCCCCUCGUGGGGCCUUGCCUUAAACUUGCCUGGUUUGUACAUUUUUUGCCGGACGCAUCAAGAAGCAAUCUGUGACAAAGUCUGAGGGUCUUCCUUUAUGCUUGCCCUCCACACUAAGAGAAGUUGGCGUCUCCCUCCUGGGAAUUGUUUUGCCUUUCUGUUCAUCUGUGAACUGUUUUUUGUUUUUAAUUACUCUGUACCCCAUCCGAAUCAGGGCUUCUACCACUGCUGAUGCAAAACCACAAAGGGACCUACCUGAGCCACCGUCCUAGCCAAGCGAGCAAACCUGCAGGGGGUUUGGAAGUGGACUUGGUCACCGCAGAAGCGUGUGCGCCGUUGGGGGAAGAGCUGCGUCACAGCCAGAGGGACAAAGUGUGGGUGAUCCUGGAGACGCCAGUUUCCGAGAUUGUUCUGCAUAUUCAUUUGCACAUUGUUGUCUGGGUUGGACAUGCGUGUGGGCUUCAGUGUGAGGCUUUUAAUAUGUAUAUCCUGUUAUCAAUAAAACAAUUAUCCAAGUGGUUGAAUCCUGUGAGACUUGGCAAGUGUGUGCAAAUCAAGUAUACUUGACUUUUCAACCUCUUCUUUCAAUGUAACUUUUAUAUGAAAUAAAGUAAUCAAUUAACAGUUCUCAAAUGGCUUCCAAAGCGCCCGUUCUUCCUGGAUGGUGGUGUUUUCAGGGGGUGCCUUUCCGUGCUUCGUGGGCCCAGCCCCAGGCUGUUAAGGUCACUCCCAAACAGUUUCCAGAAACUCUAAAUGCUUUUGUGCCCAUGACAAGUGACCUGGGCACUCAAGCGCGACUCACAAAUGUUGCCCAGUGAGUACUGUUGCUUGUUGAAUGUUUAAUUCGACUCCCAUCGUUUUACUUAGUCCUUUUUUUAGUGCACGUUGAAAUAAAAACAAUGUUUCAAAAUCUCCACA